AGUCUAAGCAAACCCCAGCAGGAAAGCAGGGGUACAGAGAGGAGCCCCCUUGGCACCGCCACCGCACCCUAGGCCACCCACCAUGGCGCUGGGCUUGGAGCAGGCGGAGGAGCAGCGGUUGUACCAGCAGACGCUCCUGCAAGACGGGCUCAAAGACAUGCUGGACCAUGGCAAGUUCCUCGACUGUGUGGUGCGGGCGGGCGAGCGCGAGUUCCCGUGCCAUCGCCUGGUGCUGGCCGCCUGCAGCCCCUACUUCCGGGCGCGCUUUCUAGCCGAGCCGGAGCGCGCGGGCGAGCUGCACCUGGAGGAGGUGUCCCCGGACGUGGUGGCCCAGGUGCUGCACUACCUGUACACAUCAGAGAUCGCGCUGGAUGAGGCGAGCGUGCAGGAUUUGUUCGCCGCGGCACACCGCUUCCAGAUCCCUUCCAUCUUCACCAUCUGCGUGUCCUUCCUGCAGAAGCGCCUGUGCCUCUCCAACUGCUUGGCCGUCUUCCGUCUCGGCCUCCUGCUCGACUGCGCGCGUCUCGCCGUGGCUGCCCGCGACUUCAUCUGCGCUCACUUCACGCUGGUGGCGCGCGACGCUGACUUCCUCGGACUCUCGGCCGACGAGCUCAUCGCCAUCAUCUCCAGCGACGGCCUUAACGUGGAGAAGGAGGAGGCAGUGUUCGAGGCGGUGAUGCGGUGGGCGGGUAGCGGCGACGCCGAGGCGCAGGCUGAGCGCCAGCGCGCGCUGCCCACCGUCUUCGAGAGCGUGCGCUGCCGCUUGCUGCCGCGCGCCUUUCUGGAAAGCCGCGUGGAGCGCCACCCUCUCGUGCGUGCCCAGCCCGAGUUGCUGCGCAAGGUGCAGAUGGUGAAGGAUGCACACGAGGGCCGCAUCACCACGCUGCGGAAGAAAAAGAAGGGGAAGGAUGGAGCCGGGGCCAAGGAGGCUGAUAAGGGCACAAGCAAAGCCAAAGCAGAGGAGGAUGAGGAGGCCGAACGUAUCCUUCCUGGGAUCCUCAAUGACACCCUGCGCUUCGGCAUGUUCCUGCAGGAUCUCAUCUUCAUGAUCAGUGAGGAGGGCGCUGUGGCCUACGAUCCAGCAGCCAACGAGUGCUACUGUGCUUCCCUCUCCAACCAGGUCCCCAAGAACCACGUCAGCCUGGUUACCAAGGAGAACCAGGUCUUCGUGGCUGGAGGCCUCUUCUACAACGAAGACAACAAAGAGGACCCCAUGAGCGCAUACUUCCUGCAGUUUGACCAUCUGGACUCAGAGUGGCUGGGGAUGCCACCGCUGCCCUCGCCCCGCUGCCUCUUUGGCCUGGGAGAAGCUCUCAACUCCAUCUACGUGGUCGGUGGCAGAGAGAUCAAGGACGGCGAGCGCUGCCUGGACUCGGUCAUGUGCUACGACAGGCUGUCAUUCAAAUGGGGUGAAUCGGACCCGCUGCCUUACGUGGUGUAUGGCCACACAGUGCUCUCCCACAUGGACCUUGUCUACGUAAUUGGCGGCAAAGGCAGUGACAGGAAGUGCCUGAACAAGAUGUGCGUCUAUGACCCCAAGAAGUUUGAGUGGAAGGAGCUGGCACCCAUGCAGACCGCCCGCUCACUCUUUGGGGCCACUGUCCAUGAUGGCCGCAUUAUCGUGGCAGCUGGGGUCACCGACACAGGGCUGACCAGUUCUGCCGAAGUGUACAGCAUCACAGACAACAAGUGGGCACCCUUCGAGGCCUUCCCACAGGAGCGUAGCUCACUCAGCCUGGUCAGCCUGGUGGGUACCCUCUAUGCCAUUGGUGGCUUUGCCACACUGGAGACGGAGUCUGGAGAGCUGGUUCCCACAGAGCUCAAUGACAUCUGGAGGUAUAACGAGGAGGAGAAGAAAUGGGAGGGUGUCCUGCGGGAGAUCGCCUAUGCAGCAGGUGCCACCUUCCUACCAGUGCGGCUCAAUGUGCUGUGCCUGACUAAGAUGUGACCAGCUCAGGCAGACUGAACUAAGCACCCCUCCCAUCCUGCGACCCUCACUGGCCUGGCCUUGUGGGGGCUCCAGAAAAGAGGCUAGGAGAGGCCAGAGUCUACCUGGAUCCAGUUAUGGUGCCUCAGGGGCUGCGUCAGCCAAGGAAAGGGAAGUGCUGCUUAGUCCUGGACUUUUGGGCAAGGGUGAGAAACUAGAGGCUUCUCCAGUGUUGCCAUAUCCCCCUAGGUUGUCUUGAUCCAUGAACCAGAACCACAGGGCGGUAUCCCAGGCCGUGUGCUGGCCCUGCCCCAGCCUAGCUGAGUGUGCUGGCAAAGUUCCCCACAGGACUCAGCCUUCUCGUCUGUCCGAUGGGAGCAUCCCCAUCAAGUGCAGUGUACAGUGCAGAUAUGUCUCCUUCUUUAGGAAGAAUAAAGUGCCUUCUGAGCAAGCAGCUCAGGGUCUGCAUCAGUGCUCCAAGAGUCAGUGAGCAGGUGUGUUGAAGACUUGGGGCUUCAGUGUUCUGCUGUUGGGCUGCCAAGGUCGAUGGUCUCUGCUCUCCAUCUGGUGUC